GCCCUGCGUUCCGUGGCGCCCCCUGGAGGGAGGAAGGGGAACUGUAUCUGAGAGAGAGCAGCCAAUUGGGUCCGCUGACUCCGGCCGGGUUCCCGUGCCGCGUCCAACACCCCUCACUCCCUGUCUCACUCCCCCACGGAGACUCAAUUUACUUUCCAUGUCCACAUCCCCAGUGCUUGCGGAAGAUAUCCCGCUAAGAGAGAGACAUGUCAAAGGUAGGGUAGAUCGACAUUUCCAGGCACCAAAGAUGGAGAUGUUCCAGGAAAGACUGCAGGGCCCCUGGGCACCUUCCACCUGCUUCCAGGCCAUCACUGGCAUGAGAAGGGGCAGACCAGUGUGAGCUGUGGAAGGAGGCCUCUUUCUGGAGGAGCGUGACCCCCAGGGCUGCUGCUGUUGCUGCUGCUGAGCAUGGGCGGGACAUGGGCAUCCAAGGAGCCGCUUCGGCCACGGUGCCGCCCCAUCAAUGCCACCCUGGCUGUGGAGAAGGAGGGCUGCCCCGUGUGCAUCACCGUCAACACCACCAUCUGUGCCGGCUACUGCCCCACCAUGACCCGCGUGCUGCAGGGGGUCCUGCCGGCCCUGCCUCAGGUGGUGUGCAACUACCGCGAUGUGCGCUUCGAGUCCAUCCGGCUCCCUGGCUGCCCGCGCGGCGUGAACCCCGUGGUCUCCUACGCCGUGGCUCUCAGCUGUCAAUGUGCACUCUGCCGCCGCAGCACCACUGACUGCGGGGGUCCCAAGGACCACCCCUUGACCUGUGAUGACCCCCGCUUCCAGGCCUCCUCUUCCUCAAAGGCCCCUCCCCCCAGCCUUCCAAGCCCAUCCCGACUCCCGGGGCCCUCAGACACCCCGAUCCUCCCACAAUAAAGGCUUCUCAAUCCGCA